GCAGAGAGCAUCGGCCGGCGACCGUUCCGGCGGCCAUUGCGAAAACUUCCCCACGGCUACUGCGUCCACGUGGCGGUGGCGUGGGGACUCCCUGAAAGCAGAGCGGCAGGGCGCCCGGAAGUCGUGAGUCGAGUCUUCCCGGGCUAAUCCAUGCCGGGUUGGAGGCUGCUGACGCAGGUCGGCGCCCAGGUGCUGGGUCGACUCGGGGACGGCCUGGGUGCUGCCCUGGGCCCGGGGAACAGAACACACAUCUGGCUUUUUGUUAGAGGUCUUCAUGGAAAGAGUGGUACAUGGUGGGAUGAGCAUCUUUCUGAAGAAAAUGUCCCAUUCAUUAAGCAGUUGGUCUCUGAUGAAGAUAAAGCCCAAUUAGCAAGUAAACUGUGUCCUCUGAAAGAUGAACCAUGGCCUAUACAUCCUUGGGAACCAGGUUCCUUUAGAGUUGGUCUUAUUGCCUUGAAGCUGGGCAUGAUGCCUUUAUGGACCAAGGAUGGUCAAAAGCAUGUGGUCACAUUACUUCAGGUACAAGACUGUCAUGUCUUAAAAUAUACGUCAAAGGAAAACUGUAAUGGAAAAAUGGCAACCCUGUCUGUAGGAGGAAAAACUGUAUCACGUUUUCGUAAAGCUACAUCCAUAUUGGAAUUUUACCGGGAACUUGGAUUGCCGCCGAAACAGACAGUUAAAAUCUUUAAUAUAACAGAUAAUGCUGCAAUUAAACCAGGCACUCCUCUUUAUGCUGCUCACUUUCGUCCAGGACAGUAUGUGGAUGUCACAGCCAAAACUAUUGGUAAAGGUUUUCAAGGUGUCAUGAAAAGAUGGGGAUUUAAAGGCCAGCCUGCUACGCAUGGUCAAACGAAAACCCACAGGAGACCUGGAGCUGUUGCAACUGGUGAUAUUGGCAGAGUCUGGCCUGGAACUAAAAUGCCUGGAAAAAUGGGAAACAUAUACAGGACAGAAUAUGGACUGAAAGUGUGGAGAAUAAACACAAAGCACAACAUAAUCUAUGUAAAUGGCUCUGUACCUGGACAUAAAAAUUGCUUAGUAAAGGUCAAAGAUUCUAAACUGCCUGCAUAUAAGGAUCUCGGUAAAAAUCUACCAUUCCCUACAUAUUUUCCUGAUGGAGAUGAAGAGGAACUGCCAGAAGAUUUGUAUGAUGAAAACGUGUGUCAGCCCGGUGCGCCUUCUAUUACAUUUGCCUAACAUCUUUGGACGUGGCAGAACCUUACAUAUUCUGUGAGCUUCGAUGAGCCAGAGUGAUAUCAUAACCACCAGAAAUCAUACUCUCCUUUCUUAGUCACAACAAAAUCACACAUGUCAUCUUUGUCAAGGGCAUAAAUAUAUCAUUCAUACCCCCAUUAAAUUUUGUUAGAAAAAUUACCACAUUAAAUAUAUGAGUUAAGUAGAUUGGAUUUGCUGAAAUUGGUGUUGGGCAUAUUAGCAAAAUAUUCUUAAUUUGUGGACUCGAUUCUUUUUUACUACAUAUUUCCCAAGUUAUCUUAAGAUGUCUGUAAAUUUAACUUUUAUUAAAGUUUUGUCAAUCUUUGUGAAAUAGUGGUUGUGGAACAGUAGAAAACCAUAUGGGGACUAUAGUGCAACCUAUUUGGGUAAAGAAACCAUUUGCUAAAAUGGAGAAAGUAAAUAGAUUUUUAUUUAAAUUACAGAAACAUGUUAAAGGCCGGACAAAGGAAAGACAAUAAAAUCAUAAAUUAUC